GAAUGGAGGAAGAACAAAGGCAGGCCCGCUUGCGGGAGAGUCAGUACGCAGCGUUGGACGCUAUGAACAGCCUCCCUGGUCCCUUUUUCAUUCUCCUUGUUUCUCCUUGUUCUUUCCCGGCCUCCCUGUAGCUCCUACUCUCUUCCUUGGUGUCCCGCCAUUUCCUUUAGUCAGUGGCAACUGUUCGGGCUACAUUUUGAAAACACUCCUUCCUUGUAAAACUUUCUGAAGUUGAAUGGAAGGUGCAAGAGCUUUAGAACAGCCAGACCUGAGUUUCAGAUCUUGGACUAGCUACGAAUAAUUUGUGACUUUGGGCAUGCAAUGGAGGAACUAUUUUACCCUAUAAACUCUGGGCCAUCAUUCAGGGAAAAGCCUGUAGAAGACCACAGUCAGAUAUUGAGUUUUGAUUCAUCAUGGAUAAUCUGUCAUCAGAAGAAAUUCAACAGAGAGCUCACCAGAUUACUGAUGAGUCUCUGGAAAGUACGAGGAGAAUCCUGGGUUUAGCCAUUGAGUCUCAGGAUGCAGGAAUCAAGACCAUCACUAUGCUGGAUGAACAAAAGGAACAACUAAACCGCAUAGAAGAAGGCUUGGACCAAAUAAAUAAGGACAUGAGAGAGACAGAGAAGACUUUAACAGAACUCAACAAAUGCUGUGGCCUUUGUGUCUGCCCAUGUAAUAGAUUCUCAGAUGUUGGUUGUUUCUAUGAAACCAGAACAAAGAACUUUGAGUCUGGCAAGGCUUAUAAGACAACAUGGGGAGAUGGUGGAGAAAACUCACCUUGCAAUGUAGUAUCUAAACAGCCAGGCCCGGUGACAAAUGGUCAGCUUCAGCAACCAACAACGGGAGCAGCCAGUGGUGGAUACAUUAAACGCAUAACUAAUGAUGCCAGAGAAGAUGAAAUGGAAGAGAACCUGACUCAAGUGGGCAGUAUCCUGGGAAAUCUAAAAGACAUGGCCCUGAACAUAGGCAAUGAGAUUGAUGCUCAAAAUCCACAAAUAAAACGAAUCACAGACAAGGCUGACACCAACAGAGAUCGUAUUGAUAUUGCCAAUGCCAGAGCAAAGAAACUCAUUGACAGCUAAAGCUACUGCUGUUCUUCUUUAUCAUUUAUUCACUUCCGUAGCUCCUCCUUGAAAGUUAUUACCUUUUCAGAGUUUAAGUUUUCGGUUCCACGCUCUUCUAAUUGGGAGAUAAUAUGGAAGAAGGGCCAGAGCAGUUACAGCCCUCCUUCUUUUUUGUUUUCUGUUGAGGGCCGACUGCUGCUCUGCCUUCCUUCUAGUAUUUUCUUUCUCAAUUCAUACGCUUAGAUUGGUUUUCAUAUGUCAUGUUUAGUGUUUUCAUCCUCCUCAUAUACUUCAGCAGGUUCUUUUGCUUUCAAGAUUUGGAAGCAUUGCCAAAGACAGCCAUGAAGAAGGAAGCUGUAGAGGUGUUUUUUGUUGUUGUUUAUUUUUGCUUUUGUGGUUGAGGGAAGGACAAGAGAUAAGAGGUUGUUACCUCAGUAAAAACCUUCAGGCCACAAAGCAAAAAGUUGCAUAGCCACAACGAAGAUCUAGUUGGAUAUAGUUUUUGAUUUAAGUUGCAGUUAUAGCCAAUUUAGGCUAAUGCUUGGUUUUGGAGCUUUUAUACACAACGUUUUUGUUAGGCAUCACAGUUUUGCAACCUCUGCUCCAAAGAGAAAAAUAGAAUGAGUUUUCUUUCUUUUUUUUUUUUUUGGAGUCAGAGUCUCGCUCUCUUGUCCAGGCUGGAGUGCAAUAGCGCGAUCUGGGCUCACUGCAACCUCCGCCUCCCUGGUUCAAGCAAUUCUCCUGCCUUGCCUCCUGAGUAGCUGGGAUUACAGGCGUGUGUCACCACGCUCGGCUAAUUUUUGUAUUUUUAGUAGAGACAGGGUUUCACCAUGUCAAGCUGGUCUUGGACUCCUGACGUCGUGAUCCACCCGCCUUGGCCUCCCAAAGUACUGGGAUUACAGGCGUGAGCCACUGUGCCUGGCUGAGUUUUCUUAAAGUGAGCUUAAUUUCUGAACUCUUAGUGAUUCAUAUAUGUACAUAAAUCUGUGAUCCCAUUUCUUAUUGCACCAUUCAGGAACACUUUAUAUAAAUGAGUGGCUUUUUAUUUCAUAUUAUUAGUAGUAUCAUGGUUCCAUUACAGGCCUAUUAACAUCAUACAUUGUCAUUAGUCUUUGAAGAAAAAAUAUGUAAAUAUAUAUGUGUAACAUGAGAAUUUCUCUCUAAAGCAGGGCUUAAAAUUUUUUGGAAAAGUUUGACAAAGCAUACCACAUGAAUUCAGAUUUACCUCAAUGCUAAGAAUUAUGUUUAGUUAGGAAAAAGGAAAGUCAUUUUGACCUCAGGUAGAAAAAUAGAUUGCUUUGAGUUUUAUGUAGCUUUAGACUUUAAAAAGUUAGAAUUUAUUCUGUAACUAAAAAUUAUUUGAAAAAAUUAUGCCUCUGGUUUAAUUAUUGGUGAUUACACACUCUUUCUCUUACCCUUGUGUAUUGAACUAUGUCCAUAAUCAAGUUGAUGUGGAUCCUGAAAAGUGUUAUGAACAUCUGAUUGGUAUUUGUCACAUUUAUUUUAAAAUUAGCAUCUGAACACUUCAAAGCUGUCAGUGUGUAUUGGUUUCACCAAUAACCACUGCUUGAUCCUUACAAUUAAAUUUUUUAACUAAC